GGGCUCCGUUCCCGGCCUCUUCGGGGACGCACGGUUGGAAGUUGUACCGUGACGUGAUGGUCAGAUCGGAUGAUAGAAUUUUGGGAACAACAAUAGCAGAGGCCUUUGUUGCCCUCUCCGCGAAACUGCCCAGUAACCUGGCAUUAGACGGGUCCCUGGCUGACCUGAUAAAGAAGCUCUACAAUUCCGUGUCCAGUCCUGGUCACCCAUAGUCUUCCAAAAUCCAGCAAGAAAAAUCCUUCUCAGAAAGGUCUCCAAUGCGUAUGACCUCAUCUUCCUUCGUAUCCUACUGCACUCCAGGACUAUGCCAAUUUAUGGCCAUGCUCCCAACAGCAGGUCACCUCCUGCCCCUCCUGCUGGUGAUAGGCACAGGGGGUACUGUGCCCAGCCCCCAGGUGCCUCCCCGGGGCUGUUAUGUGGCAAAGGAAGCAGGUGAACGGACGUUCCGCUGCAGCCAGGCAGGCCUCAGUGCUGUGCCCUCCGGCAUCCCCAAUGACACCCGCAAGCUCUACCUGGAUGCCAACCAGCUGGCAUCGGUGCCUGCUGGUGCCUUCCAGCACCUGCCUGUCCUGGAGGAGUUGGAUCUGUCCCAUAAUGCCCUUGCCCACCUCUCAGGGGCGGCUUUCCAGGGCCUGGAGGGCACAUUGCGCCACCUCGACCUCUCUGCCAACCAGCUGGCCUCAGUGCCCGUGGAGGCCUUUGUGGGGCUACAGAUCCAAGUGAACCUAUCCGCAAACCCAUGGCACUGUGACUGCGCCCUCCAGGAAGUGCUCCGGCAGGUGAGGCUGGUGCCGGGCACUGGGACAGGCAUCGUGUGUGGCUCAGGAGCCCGACCGGACCUCGUGGGGCAGGAGUUCCUGCUGCUGGCAGGGGAGGAAGAGCUGUGUGGGUCGGGGUGGGGUGGGGCCCGGAGGAGCACCGAUGUGGCCCUGCUGGUCACCAUGGGGGGCUGGCUGACACUCAUGGUGGCUUAUCUGGUGCAUUAUGUGUGGCAGAACCGAGAUGAGACCAGGCGCUCCCUCAAGCGGGCCCCAGUGCUGCCCGUGCGUUCCGAGGACUCCUCCAUCCUCAGCACAGUGGUCUGAUGACCCAGGAUGCUCCUCCAGCCACACCCCACACUCCUGCCCCUAUGCCCUCUCCUUUGCUCUGACCCCCUCUGCCUCCUGUGCAGCUUCACCCCUGCCCCCAAGCCCAUCCCACCCCUCCCUCCUUUAUUCCCCCUAAAUACCUGUGCUGGUUCUCUCUCUCUCUCUCUGUGUCGUCUUAACCAACACCAUCUUUGGUGCCUGGAGUUUUUUGGUGCCUACUCUGUGCCUGGAUUGUGCUAGACUCAGAAAACCCAUAACAGAG